AAAAGCAGCAUCAGACAAGAGCUUUAUUAAUCCCUUACACGAGCAAAUGCGAUCUCUGACCUACUAGACUUGUUUUCCUACAAUUUCACAAAAAGCCUCGCUAGAGGAAUGUGCAAGGACAGAAGGGAAACUGAGGAGACCCGCAACUCAUUAGCGAAAUAAUAGGGUGCACUUCAAUAAAAAUGCGGUCCUGAAGUGGAGCAGACUCACCGGCAAGGAGCCCGGAAAAUCGUCAGGGGCGGCGGCAAAAUACUAUCAAAUCAGCCUGGGAAGCAUCUUUUCGCUCAGCAAGUUCAAGAGAACAAAUAUGUUACAAUCCUUGCCUAUUCUUGCCUCCACUUCAUAAUGUCAUAAAAGCCACCUGGGGUGUCAUUUAUCAACCUCUCUCCAGCCCACUCUUCCAAAAUAACACUACAGUUUCCUACAUGUGUAUUUUUGCCAGGACUCCAAAGAGCCUUGCUAAAGUGGAACAAGCAAAAUCCUCCCCUGGCCUCCUGGGACUGCAGUCACCAGGCUGUCAAAGCCUCAAUACCCCACUGAGUUCCAGAGAAGGGUCUCAAAGCUGGGAGAGGAUCAAACUAACAUGGAGUAGAGAAUUGAACUGUGAAAAAGAAGCCCGAGAUUCCCCAGCGACGUGGUGUUGCAGCCCCGUUGAAGGAGUCAACUUGCAGGCUGUUAAAGACCUCAAGUCAUUAGCAUCAGCUGCUGCACUAAAGGGGCAAGUCAGCGCCUCUAAGUGGCUUAGCGCACAAACGAGGCUCCCGAGACGGCCUCGGCAACUCCAUCCCCUCCUCCACCACCCGCUGGAUGUGAAAAGCUUUCCGGAGCCCAUCUUGGGGGAAGCUUGGUAGUGUUGGCGCUCCUGAAGAGAGACGACGCCCGUUUAUCACCCCCAGGCAACUAGCUGCGCAAAUCAGCGGUGGCUCCAGGGCUAGAGAAUCCCUGGAGCUAACCGCACCCCUCUCCCUUUCACGGAACGCGGACUCCGGGGAAAUACGCACGGGGUCCGCACGCGCUGGGUGUCCAGCUCUCUGUCACAGCUUCUCCAAGUGCCUAGUGAAACGGGGAAAGGCCCUCUCCAAUCAUUUUGGAAGAGCCUAAAAGGCGGCAACACCAACACCUCUUGACAUGGAAAUACACUGAUACAAUAGGCAAAAGGAAACACUCGAUUGCAUCUUCCCGGUUCCAGGUGGCCUUAUUUGGGAGAUUCUAUACUGACCUUAUUCCUGUGAUGGAGGAUACUGGCAUCCAGCGAGGCAUCUGGGAUGGAGAUGCCAAGGCUGUCCAACAAUGUCUGACAGAUAUUUUUACCAGCGUUUACACCACCUGCGACAUCCCUGAGAAUGCUAUAUUUGGUCCCUGUGUCCUGAGCCAUACUUCCCUAUAUGACAGCAUAGCUUUCAUAGCUCUCAAGUCUACUGACAAGAGAACAGUACCGUAUAUCUUUCGGGUAGACACCUCAGCAGCAAAUGGUUCCUCAGAAGGUCUCAUGUGGCUGCGGUUGGUCCAAUCGGCCAGAGAUAAGGAAGAGCAGAACCUUGAAGCCUACAUAAAAAACGGACAGCUGUUCUACCGCUCUCUCCGCAGGAUUGCCAAAGACGAGGAGUUACUAGUUUGGUACGGGAAAGAACUGACUGAGUUACUCUUGCUCUGCCCCUCUAGAUCCCACAACAAAAUGAAUGGGUCGUCCCCUUACACAUGCCUGGAAUGCAGCCAACGUUUCCAGUUUGAGUUCCCCUAUGUGGCGCAUCUGCGUUUCCGCUGCCCCAAGAGACUUCACAGCGCUGAUAUAAGUCCCCAAGACGAACAAGGCGGCGGCGUGGGCACCAAGGACCACGGGGGCGGCGGCGGCGGUGGCAAAGACCAGCAGCAGCAGCAGCAGGAGGCACCUUUAGGCCCGGGUCCCAAGUUUUGCAAAGCCGGCCCCCUCCACCACUACCCAUCCCCCUCCCCGGAAAGCAGCAACCCAUCCGCUGCCGCCGGCGGCAGCAGCGCGAAGCCAUCCACAGACUUCCACAACCUGGCCAGGGAGCUGGAAAACUCCCGGGGAGGCAGCAGCUGCUCCCCAGCCCAGAGCCUCAGCAGCGGUAGCGGCAGCGGCGGCGGCGGCGGCCACCAGGAGGCGGAGCUGAGUCCCGACGGCAUCGCCACGGGCGGCGGCAAAGGAAAGAGGAAAUUCCCGGAGGAGGCGGCGGAGGGCGGCGGUGGCGCUGGUCUGGUAGGGGGCCGGGGCCGCUUCGUAGAGCGGCCCCUCCCGGCCUCCAAGGAGGAUCUGGUGUGCACACCGCAGCAGUACCGAGCCUCGGGCAGCUACUUCGGCCUGGAAGAGAACGGCCGCCUCUUCGCGCCGCCAAGUCCCGAGACGGGCGAGGCGAAGCGCAGCGCCUUCGUGGAGGUGAAGAAGGCUGCCCGCGCGGCCAGCCUGCAGGAGGAGGGGACAGCCGACGGCGCGGGAGUCGCCUCCGAGGACCAGGACGCUGGCGGCGGCGGCGGCUCCUCCACGCCCGCGGCCGCGUCACCGGUGGGCGCCGAGAAGCUGCUGGCCCCGCGGCCUGGGGGCCCGCUGCCCAGCCGGCUCGAGGGCGGCAGUCCUGCGAGGGGCAGCGCCUUCACUUCGGUGCCGCAGCUGGGCAGCGCGGGCAGCACCAGCGGUGGGGGCGGAACGGGCGCCGGGGCCGCAGGCGGCGCGGGCGGGGGCCAGGGCGCCGCGUCGGACGAGCGCAAAAGCGCCUUCUCGCAGCCAGCACGCUCUUUCUCGCAGCUGUCCCCGCUGGUGCUGGGCCAGAAGCUGGGCGCGCUCGAGCCAUGCCACCCCGCCGACGGCGUGGGCCCCACCAGACUCUAUCCCGCCGCCGCGGACCCUCUAGCGGUGAAGCUCCAGGGGGCCGCGGACCUGAACGGAGGUUGCGGGUCCCUGCCGAGCGGCGGCGGCGGCCUGCCUAAGCAGAGCCCCUUCCUGUACGCCACCGCCUUCUGGCCCAAGAGCUCCGCUGCCGCUGCAGCCGCGGCUGCGGCGGCGGCCGCGGGGCCCUUGCAGCUGCAGCUGCCCUCGGCGCUCACGCUGCUGCCGCCCUCCUUCACCUCGCUGUGUCUGCCCGCGCAGAACUGGUGCGCCAAGUGCAAUGCCUCCUUCCGCAUGACCUCCGACCUGGUGUACCAUAUGAGGUCGCACCACAAAAAGGAGUAUGCGAUGGAGCCCUUGGUGAAGCGGCGGCGAGAGGAGAAACUCAAGUGCCCCAUCUGCAAUGAGUCCUUCAGGGAGCGCCACCACCUCUCCAGGCACAUGACCUCGCAUAAUUGACUCGGAAAGGACCCCAGCUUUCCACGCGCGCGCAAGCACAGUUAAGCCACCUGCAGGAAUAAACACGCGAGAACAUCCACCGCUUCCUUGCACCCCGAAACCCUGCACAAAGACACAUACAUUCACCGCCCCCCCGCCCCCCCAACGCGCACACACACGUCCUCUCCUCCCAGGAACCUCAUUCAAAUAUUUACCCGGGACACACACCCCCCCCCACACACACACACAGACACACUCACACACAAGAGCCAGGAUGGUGGAGUUUUGAUUGGGUGGGUUGUUUGAGGGGGUUUUCUUUUGAAUGCACGCAUUUUCACUUUCCCCAAAACAAAGGUACAUUUUUUAAAAUGUCAUAUAUUGCAACAUAUUGAUGCAUUUGUCAUACGUUUCUACUUAAAUUAUUAAGCACUUACGAUUUAGAUGUAAUAAUUAUAUGUAAGGGCAAAAUUUAUUUUAGAUAUAAAGUAAAGGAGGAGGGUGAGAUGCUUUCUGCAUUUCUUGAUGACAGUUUGUGUUCCUACAAAAAUAAACAAAAUGAAUAAAAAGGGAUCACCAUUCAAUUUGAGUUUCCAGGGGGAAGUGCAUGUAUAAUGAAAUGAUAAUGGACUUCAAUGAAGAAUGUCAUCAAUUAUGUACAUAUGUAUUUUCUUUUAAUACAAAGUGUAAUUUUGUGCCAGUGAAAUGGAGUCUGAAUAGUUAUGUGUUUCUUUUAUCCCUGGAAAUAUUUAUUAAACUUUAUAGUUUAUCCGAGUAUGUUGGAUGCUUUGACAAUAAAUGACUAUUUUCUUCAAAGCAAA